AGAACAUAGGUUGCCUUAGAGAGGUUCCCCGGUGUCCCGACGGCGGCUCAAGUCAGAGUUGCUGGGUUUUGCUCAGAUUGGUGUGGGAAGAGCCUGCCUGUGGGGAGCGGCCACUCCAUACUGCUGAGGCCUCAGGACUGCUGCUCAGCUUGCCCGUUACCUGAAGAGGCGGCGGAGCCGGGCCCCUGACCGGUCACCAUGUGGGCCUUCUCGGAAUUGCCCAUGCCGCUGCUGAUCAAUUUGAUCGUCUCGCUGCUGGGAUUUGUGGCCACAGUCACCCUCAUCCCGGCCUUCCGGGGCCACUUCAUUGCUGCGCGCCUCUGUGGUCAGGACCUCAACAAAACCAGCCGACAGCAGAUCCCAGAAUCCCAGGGAGUGAUCAGCGGUGCUGUUUUCCUUAUCAUCCUCUUCUGCUUCAUCCCUUUCCCCUUCCUGAACUGCUUUGUGAAGGAGCAGUGUAAGGCAUUCCCCCACCAUGAAUUUGUGGCCCUGAUAGGUGCCCUCCUUGCCAUCUGCUGCAUGAUCUUCCUGGGCUUUGCGGAUGAUGUACUGAAUCUGCGCUGGCGCCAUAAGCUGCUGCUACCUACAGCUGCCUCACUACCUCUCCUCAUGGUCUAUUUCACCAACUUUGGCAACACGACCAUUGUGGUGCCCAAGCCCUUCCGCCCGAUACUUGGCCUGCAUCUGGACUUGGGAAUCCUGUACUAUGUCUACAUGGGGCUGCUGGCAGUGUUCUGUACCAAUGCCAUCAAUAUCCUAGCAGGAAUUAACGGCCUAGAGGCUGGCCAGUCACUAGUCAUUUCUGCUUCCAUCAUUGUCUUCAACCUGGUAGAGUUGGAAGGUGAUUGUCGGGAUGAUCAUGUCUUUUCCCUCUACUUCAUGAUACCCUUUUUUUUCACCACUUUGGGAUUGCUCUACCACAACUGGUACCCAUCACGGGUGUUUGUGGGAGAUACCUUCUGUUACUUUGCUGGCAUGACCUUUGCCGUGGUGGGCAUCUUGGGACACUUCAGCAAGACCAUGCUACUAUUCUUCAUGCCCCAGGUGUUCAACUUCCUCUACUCACUGCCUCAGCUCCUGCAUAUCAUCCCCUGCCCUCGCCACCGCAUACCCAGACUCAAUAUCAAGACAGGCAAACUGGAGAUGAGCUAUUCCAAGUUCAAGACCAAGAGCCUCUCUUUCUUGGGCACCUUUAUUUUAAAGGUGGCAGAGAGCCUCCAGCUGGUGACAGUACACCAGAGUGAGACUGAAGAUGGUGAAUUCACUGAAUGUAACAACAUGACCCUCAUCAACUUGCUACUUAAAGUCCUUGGGCCCAUACAUGAGAGAAACCUCACAUUGCUCCUGCUGCUGCUGCAGAUCCUGGGCAGUGCCAUCACCUUCUCCAUUCGAUAUCAGCUCGUUCGACUCUUCUAUGAUGUCUGAGUCCCUUGAUCAUUGUCCUUUACCUCACAGUCUCUAGGAUUCCUGACUCAGGCUGACCUCUCUCUCUGGUCCCAGACUGCCUCCUUGCCCAGGCCUCUCUCACUCUUCAUACUCCUCCAGAUUUUGUUCUCAGCAUUUUCCUUUCUCUGUGAUCAUUGGCAUCCUGGGCGUUUCUUGCCCUCUGCUGACUACUGAUUGGAUUUUACCUAUGGCUUUCUGCAACUUGCUACUCUCUCCCUCUCCAUCCCAUCUUUGCAGCCUCAUAGGGUGGGAUACAGCAGCUUUUUUUGCAGUUAUCCACACUCACAUUUCAGAGUCCUGACUCUCAAGGAACCACUGGUUUUUGGGAUAGAACUUGGGCCAGGGCUAGGAACACAGGCUCCACGGUGACAUGUCAUUUGAUUGUAAAUUAAGUGUUCUGAUUAGUAAGAACUAAGCAGGGGGCCACAUGCUCUCAAUGGAGACAAUAAAGUGUUGUCUUUUUCUUAUUGUUUAUGUAGGUAUAUUUCCUAUAUGGGCAUUUUUGGGUAGAUUGGGAGGGGUGGUGGGGGUACUUCCUCCAACAGGAUGCCUAUCUCUCUGCCCCAUCAGACCCCGUCUAACAAGAAGUGAACAGAACUGAGACCAAACAGAACAUAUUGAAUAAAUAUUUAAAUCCUGAUACUAGAGGUGGCAUGGAGGGCCACAAAAUUGAAGUUAUCCUGUUUCCUGGCAUGGGAACAAACUUUCAAAGAGUCACCGGGUGCAGUGGCUCAUGCCUGUAAUCCCAGCACUUUAGGAGGCUGAGGCAGGAGGAUUGCCUGAGCCCAGGAAUUCAAGACAGCCUGGGCAACAAAACGAGACUCCGUCUCUACAAAAAUAAAAUAAUUAGCCAAGUGUGGUGGAGCACUUGUAGUACCAGCUACGAGGGAGGUUUAGCAGGGAGGAUUCCUUGAACCCAGGAGUUCGAGGCUGCAGUGAGCUGAGAUCACACUACUGCACUCCAGCCUGGGUGACAGAGCCAGUGACACCCGGUCUAUUAAAAAAAGAAAGAAAGAAAAAAAAGAAAACUUUUAAGGGGUCUAAUUUCUUCACUUUUCCAUUCUCCCUUUGUCAGGUAGGAGAAGGGAGUAGGGAGUGACUGGACCUGGAAAGGAGGGCUGCAGUAGCUAUAAUAUUGACCCCUUUCCUUUAAAAAUCCUACGCCGGCACAGAUUUCCCAGACGCUCUCUAGGUGGCCUCAGACUCCACCCCUUUGGUCUUCCGCUUCUGGUUUCCGAUUGUAGUGUUUAAAUCUCGCGCGCUUUACAAGGAUUGGCUACAUCAGCGGAUAGUUGGCAGUCUGCGUGCUACCCCUCCUCCUCGCCUUUUCUCCCCGGGCAAAAGGUUUUCAAAUUCGACCAAUCAGCGGGCGCGCUCCCUCAGCCGAGCCGCGACACCCAAGGGUUAACCGCAACCAACCGGAGGCGGGUAUUGGAGAAAAGAGCCAAUCAGGAGGGCGCAGAGGUGUGUCCUGGGGGCUUAUAAAGGCGGCCUCGCGGCGCGCGCGCGACAGCAGUUACACUGCGGCGGGCGUCUGUUCUAGUGUUUGAGCCGUCGUGCUUCACCGGUCUACCUCGCUAGCAUGUCGGGCCGCGGCAAGACUGGCGGCAAGGCCCGCGCCAAGGCCAAGUCGCGCUCGUCGCGCGCCGGCCUCCAGUUCCCAGUGGGCCGUGUACACCGGCUGCUGCGGAAGGGCCACUACGCCGAGCGCGUUGGCGCCGGCGCGCCAGUGUACCUGGCGGCAGUGCUGGAGUACCUCACCGCUGAGAUCCUGGAGCUGGCGGGCAAUGCGGCCCGCGACAACAAGAAGACGCGAAUCAUCCCCCGCCACCUGCAGCUGGCCAUCCGCAACGACGAGGAGCUCAACAAGCUGCUGGGCGGCGUGACGAUCGCCCAGGGAGGCGUCCUGCCCAACAUCCAGGCCGUGCUGCUGCCCAAGAAGACCAGCGCCACCGUGGGGCCGAAGGCGCCCUCGGGCGGCAAGAAGGCCACCCAGGCCUCCCAGGAGUACUAAGAGGGCCCGCGCCGCGGCCGGCCGCCAGGCCUCCCCAUGCCACCACAAAGGCCCUUUUAAGGGCCACCACCGCCCUCAUGGAAAGAGCUGAGCCGCUUCAGACUGCGGGGCAAGCGGGCCGCGGCUCCCUUCCCCUCCCCUCCCCUCGCCCGCCUUCGCCGCCCGGCCUCGAGUCCCCGCCCGCCCCCGCUCCCGUCCCGCACCGCCUGCCGCGUCGGCCUCGGGCCCUGCCCUGUCCGCCGUCCGCCCUCCGGUAGGGUUCGGGCCUUCCGGAUGCGGCUUGGGCGCUCUUCGGGGACCUCCGUGGCGCGGAAGACCCGAGCCUGCCGGGGGGAGGCCGGCGGCGCCGCACCUGCCCGCCUCGGCGUUCGUGACUCAGCCGCCCCAUCCCGAGUCGCUAAGGGGCUGCGGGGAGGCCGCAGCACCUUCUGGAAGACUUGGCCUUCCGCUCUGACGCAGGGCCGAGGUGGGCAGUCCAGGCCGAGAGGCCGGCGGCCCUGAAGGUCUGCGCUGGGGCCGGGACGAAGCACUUGGUAACAGGCACAUCUUCCUCCCGAGUGACUGCCUCCUAGGAGGACAUUUAGGGGAGGGCAGAGGCCUGCAGUUUGGCUUCACGGCUGGCUAUGUGGACAGCAAGAGUCGUUUUCGCGGAAGCCGACUGGCAGCCAGGCCUGUCGGGCCCCCCGACGCCGCCCCAUUUCCCUUCCAGCAAACUCAACUCGGCAAUCCAAGCACCUAGAUACCAGCACAAGUCGGUUAAUCCCUGUCUGGACUGAGCCUCCGUUGGCUUCUGAACUGGAAUUCUGCAGCUAACCCUUCCACGACUAGAACCUUAGGCAUUGGGGAGUUUUAGAUGGACUAAUUUUAUUAAAGGAUUGUUUUUUUUUUAAA